AUUCUUGUCUUACCCUCUGCAAAUGUGAUAGGCACAGGACAGGAGUAGGCACCUCGCCUACUGCUGCUUAACCUUUCAGCUUCUCCAGGCCCCCAAUCCUGCUUGCUCCCAGCUUGGUGGGGUUUUGCCCCACCCCUGAACGCCCUCUGUGGCGCCUUCCACCCACCUGUAGGCCCAGAAGGAUGUCGGUCUGCUACCGUCCCCCAGGGAACGAGACACUGCUGAGCUGGAAGACUUCGCGGGCCACAGGCACAGCCUUCCUGCUGCUGGCGGCGCUGCUGGGGCUGCCUGGCAACGGCUUCGUGGUGUGGAGCUUGGCGGGCUGGCGGCCUGCACGGGGGCGACCGCUGGCGGCCACGCUUGUGCUGCACCUGGCGCUGGCCGACGGCGCGGUGCUGCUGCUCACGCCGCUCUUUGUGGCCUUCCUGACCCGGCAGGCCUGGCCGCUGGGCCAGGCGGGCUGCAAGGCGGUGUACUACGUGUGCGCGCUCAGCAUGUACGCCAGCGUGCUGCUCACCGGCCUGCUCAGCCUGCAGCGCUGCCUCGCAGUCACCCGCCCCUUCCUGGCGCCUCGGCUGCGCAGCCCGGCCCUGGCCCGCCGCCUGCUGCUGGCGGUCUGGCUGGCCGCCCUGUUGCUCGCCGUCCCGGCCGCCGUCUACCGCCACCUGUGGAGGGACCGCGUAUGCCAGCUGUGCCACCCGUCGCCGGUCCACGCCGCCGCCCACCUGAGCCUGGAGACUCUGACCGCUUUCGUGCUUCCUUUCGGGCUGAUGCUCGGCUGCUACAGCGUGACGCUGGCACGGCUGCGGGGCGCCCGCUGGGGCUCCGGGCGGCACGGGGCGCGGGUGGGCCGGCUGGUGAGCGCCAUCGUGCUUGCCUUCGGCUUGCUCUGGGCCCCCUACCACGCAGUCAACCUUCUGCAGGCGGUCGCAGCGCUGGCUCCACCGGAAGGGGCCUUGGCGAAGCUGGGCGGAGCCGGCCAGGCGGCGCGAGCGGGAACUACGGCCUUGGCCUUCUUCAGUUCUAGCGUCAACCCGGUGCUCUACGUCUUCACCGCUGGAGAUCUGCUGCCCCGGGCAGGUCCCCGUUUCCUCACGCGGCUCUUCGAAGGCUCUGGGGAGGCCCGAGGGGGCGGCCGCUCUAGGGAAGGGACCAUGGAGCUCCGAACUACCCCUCAGCUGAAAGUGGUGGGGCAGGGCCGCGGCAAUGGAGACCCGGGGGGUGGGAUGGAGAAGGACGGUCCGGAAUGGGACCUUUGACAGCAGACCCUACAACCUGCUGCCCUUCCCUGUCCCUUUCCACCCCCCACCCACCCUCCAGAGGUCAGUGUUCUGGGACAUUUGGGGACCCUUCUUUGACUAGAGUUUGGAUCUGGCUGGGUAGGAUUACUAUACACUUGGGGCAGGCCCAGGCUCCUCCAAACUGAGGGAUUAUGAGGGUGGUGAUGGUCCCUGUUAAGGACUAUUGUGUGCUUGCAAGUUGGCAUGUACCCAUGUGCCAGCAUUGCUUACUUGUUGCCAAUAGCUGUUAUUGUGAAAUACACUGGGAAGCCAUUA